AUUCCAGAGAGCCCAGCGAGCUAGAGCAACAAAGGAGCCGGGUCGCCGGCGGGGAGAGUUCGGGGGGCUGCGGCGCGCUGGGGCGAAGGUGGCUGCUGGGCCGCGGGCUGGCGCGGGGGCGGAGCCGGAGCUGCACUCGCACCCCCGGCCCGCGUCUGGCCUCCCUCGCGGGGCGGGGAGGUGGCUUUAAUGGUGGGAGAGGGAAUGGGGCUGGGGAUUGGGGGCCCAGGGGUCUCCUAGGGCUGAAGACAACUUGGAUUGCGAGGCUAGGGCUUGGGGAGUCGUGCAUCCCGUUCCGGGCCUCCGCAGCCCAACAUGGGCCCCGGGUUCCAAAGUUUGCGAAGUUGGGCGCCGAGGGGCCGGGGCGCGCGGAGCGUCCGGGGGGGCCCGGGCCCGGAUUCUCUGGGCGCACAGGUCGCCUGAGCCGCCUCCGCGGCCGCCGAGGUCGUGCGUGUGGCCGGGGGGCUCCGAGGAGCAGGCGGGGGCGCCGGGGCUUUUGCUGAGUUGGCGGGGUUGGCCAUGGCCGCUGCCCGCCCAGCGCGGGGGCCGGAGCUCCCGCUCCUGGGGCUGCUGCUGCUGCUGCUGCUGGGGGACCCGGGCCGGGGGGCGGCCUCGAGCGGGAACGCGACCGGGCCUGGGCCUCGGAGCGCGGGCGGGAGCGCGAGGAGGAGCGCGGCGGUGACUGGCCCUCCGCCGCCGCUGAGCCACUGCGGCCGGGCUGCCCCCUGCGAGCCGCUGCGCUACAACGUGUGCCUGGGCUCGGUGCUGCCCUACGGGGCCACCUCCACACUGCUGGCCGGAGACUCGGACUCCCAGGAGGAAGCGCACGGCAAGCUCGUGCUCUGGUCGGAGCCUCUUCUGUUCCUCUCCAUCUGACUUCCUGCUUCCUCCUCUGGCUUUGGAGUGCCUGGCUCCUCUGACUACCUCUUCUUAAGCCCCCAUCUCUUCUCUCUCACUCCGCUUGGCCUCCGGAAUGCCCCCCGCUGCUGGGCAGUGAUCCAGCCCCUGCUGUGUGCCGUAUACAUGCCCAAGUGUGAGAAUGACCGGGUGGAGCUGCCCAGCCGUACCCUCUGCCAGGCCACCCGAGGCCCCUGUGCCAUCGUGGAGAGGGAGCGGGGCUGGCCUGACUUCCUGCGCUGCACUCCUGACCGCUUCCCUGAAGGCUGCACGAAUGAGGUGCAGAACAUCAAGUUCAACAGUUCAGGCCAGUGCGAAGUGCCCUUGGUUCGGACAGACAACCCCAAGAGCUGGUACGAGGACGUGGAGGGCUGCGGCAUCCAGUGCCAGAACCCGCUCUUCACAGAGGCUGAGCACCAGGACAUGCACAGCUACAUCGCGGCCUUCGGGGCCGUCACGGGCCUCUGCACGCUCUUCACCCUGGCCACAUUCGUGGCUGACUGGCGGAACUCGAAUCGCUACCCUGCUGUUAUUCUCUUCUACGUCAAUGCGUGCUUCUUUGUGGGCAGCAUUGGCUGGCUGGCCCAGUUCAUGGAUGGUGCCCGCCGAGAGAUCGUCUGCCGUGCAGAUGGCACCAUGAGGCUUGGGGAGCCCACCUCCAAUGAGACUCUGUCCUGCGUCAUCAUCUUUGUCAUCGUGUACUACGCCCUGAUGGCUGGUGUGGUUUGGUUUGUGGUCCUCACCUAUGCCUGGCACACUUCCUUCAAAGCCCUGGGCACCACCUACCAGCCUCUCUCGGGCAAGACCUCCUACUUCCACCUGCUCACCUGGUCACUCCCCUUUGUCCUCACUGUGGCAAUCCUUGCUGUGGCGCAGGUGGAUGGGGACUCUGUGAGUGGGAUUUGUUUUGUGGGCUACAAGAACUACCGAUACCGUGCGGGCUUCGUGCUGGCCCCAAUCGGCCUGGUGCUCAUCGUGGGAGGCUACUUCCUCAUCCGAGGAGUCAUGACUCUGUUCUCCAUCAAGAGCAACCACCCCGGGCUGCUGAGUGAGAAGGCUGCCAGCAAGAUCAACGAGACCAUGCUGCGCCUGGGCAUUUUUGGCUUCCUGGCCUUUGGCUUUGUGCUCAUUACCUUCAGCUGCCACUUCUACGACUUCUUCAACCAGGCUGAGUGGGAGCGCAGCUUCCGGGACUAUGUGCUAUGUCAGGCCAAUGUGACCAUCGGGCUGCCCACCAAGCAGCCCAUCCCUGACUGUGAGAUCAAGAAUCGCCCGAGCCUUCUGGUGGAGAAGAUCAACCUGUUUGCCAUGUUUGGAACUGGCAUCGCCAUGAGCACCUGGGUCUGGACCAAGGCCACGCUGCUCAUCUGGAGGCGUACCUGGUGCAGGUUGACUGGGCAGAGUGACGAUGAGCCAAAGCGGAUCAAGAAGAGCAAGAUGAUUGCCAAGGCCUUCUCUAAGCGGCACGAGCUCCUGCAGAACCCAGGCCAGGAGCUGUCCUUCAGCAUGCACACUGUGUCCCACGACGGGCCCGUGGCGGGCUUGGCCUUUGACCUCAAUGAGCCCUCAGCUGAUGUCUCCUCUGCCUGGGCCCAGCAUGUCACCAAGAUGGUGGCUCGGAGAGGAGCCAUACUGCCCCAGGAUAUUUCUGUCACCCCUGUGGCAACUCCAGUGCCCCCAGAGGAACAAGCCAACCUGUGGCUGGUUGAGGCAGAGAUCUCCCCAGAGCUGCAGAAGCGCCUGGGCCGGAAGAAGAAGAGGAGGAAGAGGAAGAAGGAGGUGUGCCCGCUGGCGCCGCCCCCUGAGCUUCACCCCCCUGCCCCUGCCCCCAGUACCAUUCCUCGACUGCCUCAGCUGCCCCGGCAGAAAUGCCUGGUGGCUGCAGGUGCCUGGGGAGCUGGGGACUCUUGCCGACAGGGAGCGUGGACCCUGGUCUCCAACCCAUUCUGCCCAGAGCCCAGUCCCCCUCAGGAUCCAUUUCUGCCCAGUGCACCGGCCCCCGUGGCAUGGGCUCAUGGCCGCCGACAGGGCCUGGGGCCUAUUCACUCCCGCACCAACCUGAUGGACACAGAACUCAUGGAUGCAGACUCGGACUUCUGAGCCUGCAGAGCAGGACCUGGGACAGGAAAGAGAGGAACCAAUACCUUCAAGGCUCUUCUUCCUCACCGAGCAUGCUUCCCUAGGAUCCCGUCUUCCAGAGAACCUGUGGGCUGACUGCCCUCCGAAGAGAGUUCUGGAUGUCUGGCUCAAAGCAGCAGGACUGUGGGAAAGAGCCUAACAUCUCCAUGGGGAGGCCUCACCCCAGGGACAGGGCCCUGGAGCUCAGGGUCCUUGUUUCUGCCCUGCCAGCUGCAGCCUGGUUGGCAGCAUCUGCUCCAUCGGGGCAGGGGGUAUGCAGAGCUUGUGGUGGGGCAGGAACGGUGGAGGCAGAGGUGACAGUUCCCAGAGUGGGCUUUGGUGGCCAGGGAGGCAGCCUAGCCUAUGUCUGGCAGAUGAGGGCUGGCUGCCGUUUUCUGGGCUGAUGGGUGCCCUUUCCUGGCAGUCUCAGUCCAAAAGUGUUGACUGUGUCAUUAGUCCUUUGUCUAAGUAGGGCCAGGGCACCGUAUUCCUCUCCCAGGUGUUUGUGGGGCUGGAAGGACCUGCUCCCACAGGGGCCAUGUCCUCUCUUAAUAGGUGGCACUACCCCAAACCCAUCUUUUGUUCUCCUAUAUCCUCCUUCUUCUGUUCCAUUUCAGUUCAGUUUCAGCGGUGCCAACCUCUUUGCGUUUCCUUUUUGUUGAUGAGGACCCAGAGCUGCUGCACACACUCACCUCUAACCCCCUCCCCUCGCUGCUGGGCCCCAUCUCCACAGGAGAGACUGGUUCAGCUCUAGGGCCUCAGUCUGGAGUGGGAUAGGAGCAGUGAGUGACAAAGCCUCUGAAAGAUGCAUCAUCUCUUCCUCACACCCAUUUAGUGGGGGAUGGGUCCUCUAGACUUGAGGGGCUACCCUGGGAAGCUGCCGUAGCUUCAGCCAGGCAAGAAAGCUUCCUUCAACCUGCAUAGCCGGUGGGUGAGGAGAUUCCCACCUUCCAUAGCCUCCAAACAUGUUCCCAAGGCCCCACUUUCAAGAAUCAGACAGCAGGAAGCCAUAGAUGCUGGCUGGGUUCCAGGUUAUGGGGAGAAGAAAUACAGUCAAUAAAAGGUUUUUGUAUAAA